GGAGCCGCGCGAACAUGGCCGAAGUCGGCGAGGACAGCGGCGCCCGCGCCCUGCUCGCGCUGCGCUCGGCGCCCUGCAGCCCAGUGCUGUGCGCCGCAGCCGCCGCCGCCGCCUUCCCCGCGGCCGCACCCCCGCCGGCCCCCGCGCAGCCCCAGCCUCCGCCCGGGCCGCCGCCGCCGCCGCCACCGCCGCUGCCUCCGGGCGCGAUCGCGGGCGCGGGCUCCUCCGGGGGCUCCUCCGGGGUAUCCGGGGACUCCGCGGUCGCGGGCGCGGCGCCGGCCCUGGUGGCCGCGGCGGCCGCCUCGGUACGGCAGAGCCCGGGGCCGGCGCUGGCGCGGCUGGAGGGCCGCGAGUUCGAGUUCCUCAUGCGCCAGCCCAGCGUCACCAUCGGCCGCAACUCGUCGCAGGGCUCGGUGGACUUGAGCAUGGGCCUGUCCAGCUUCAUCUCGCGGCGCCACCUGCAGCUCAGCUUCCAGGAGCCGCACUUCUACCUGCGCUGCCUCGGCAAGAACGGCGUCUUCGUGGACGGGGCCUUCCAGAGACGCGGCGCGCCCGCCCUGCAGCUGCCCAAGCAGUGUACCUUCCGGUUUCCCAGCACGGCCAUCAAGAUCCAGUUCACGUCGCUCUAUCACAAAGAAGAGGCCCCAGCCUCCCCGCUGCGGCCACUGUACCCCCAGAUCUCCCCUCUGAAGAUCCACAUCCCGGAGCCGGACCUCCGGAGCAUGGUCAGCCCCGUCCCCUCCCCGACGGGCACCAUCAGUGUCCCCAACUCCUGCCCAGCCAGUCCACGCGGUGCCGGCUCCUCCAGUUACCGCUUUGUGCAGAACGUGACCUCGGACCUGCAGCUGGCAGCAGAGUUUGCAGCAAAGGCCGCGUCGGAGCAGCAGGCAGACACGUCUGGAGGAGACAGCCCCAAGGAUGAGUCAAAGCCGCCGUUCUCCUACGCGCAGCUGAUCGUGCAGGCCAUCUCCUCCGCCCAGGACCGGCAGCUGACCCUGAGCGGGAUCUACGCCCACAUCACCAAGCAUUACCCCUACUACCGGACGGCCGACAAAGGCUGGCAGAAUUCUAUCCGGCACAACCUCUCUUUGAACCGUUACUUUAUCAAAGUCCCACGUUCCCAGGAGGAGCCUGGGAAGGGGUCCUUUUGGCGAAUAGACCCUGCCUCUGAAGCCAAGCUCGUGGAACAGGCAUUCCGGAAACGGAGGCAGAGGGGUGUCUCCUGCUUCCGCACCCCCUUCGGGCCUCUGUCCUCAAGGAGCGCUCCAGCUUCGCCCACACACCCCGGGCUGAUGUCCCCUCGCUCCGGCGGCCUGCAGACCCCAGAGUGCCUGUCUCGGGAGGGCUCCCCCAUUCCACACGACCCUGAGUUUGGGUCCAAGUUAGCUUCUGUCCCAGAGUACCGGUAUUCCCAAAGCGCACCCGGCUCCCCCGUCAGCGCCCAGCCAGUGAUCAUGGCCGUGCCUCCCCGACCGUCCAGCCUCGUGGCCAAGCCCGUGGCCUACAUGCCCGCCUCCAUCGUAACCUCACAGCAGCCCGCGGGCCACGCCAUCCACGUCGUGCAGCAGGCCCCCACCGUCACCAUGGUCAGGGUGGUCACCACAUCUGCCAACUCGGCCAACGGAUACAUCCUCACCAGCCAGGGCGCGGCGGGGGGCUCCCAUGAUGCGGCGGGCGCAGCCGUGCUGGACCUGGGCAGCGAGGCCAGAGGCCUGGAGGAGAAACCCACCAUUGCGUUUGCCACAAUCCCCGCGGCUGGUGGAGUCAUCCAGACGGUGGCCAGCCAGAUGGCCCCCGGGGUCCCCGGACACACGGUCACCAUCCUGCAGCCCGCCACACCCGUGACCCUCGGGCAGCACCACCUUCCAGUCCGGGCCGUGACCCAGAACGGAAAGCAUGCGGUUCCCACGAACAGUUUAGCCGGCAACGCUUACGCCCUCACCAGCCCUUUGCAGCUCCUUGCGACCCAAGCGAGUUCAUCCGCGCCGGUGGUGGUCACCCGGGUGUGCGAGGUGGGGCCCAAGGAGCCAGCAGCAGCCGUCGCGGCCACGGCCACCACCACCCCAGCCACUGCCACCACCGCCUCUGCCUCCGCCUCUUCCACUGGAGAGCCCGAGGUCAAAAGGUCCCGGGUGGAGGAGCCCAGUGGUGCUGUAACCACACCGGCUGGAGUGAUCGCAGCUGCCGGCCCCCAGGGGCCAGGCACCGGGGAGUGAGGUCACCUGCAACGCGGGGGAGUGGGACUCACCCAGCGGCGACCCCGAAGCUGGACCCGGCAGCUCAGGCGGCCGCACCCACAGACGGAGGAGAACAGCCCGCGGCGGCCUGUGGGCAUCGGCGGCACCUGGACACACCCAGCCCUUUCCAUUUGAUCGCCUGCCUUCCCGUGGUUUAAGACAAAAACACAUAAACAAGUUCAGACAACUGAUUGUAUGAUUCUGGGAAUUCUUUGCUUUCCUUUCCUUCUCCCUCGGCACCACCUCCUCUCCCCAGGCCUCCCUGUCGGGCAUGGGGAGGAGGUUGGAGCUCAGCAUCUUGAGGAAUGUGUCAAGACAGCCCCUCCGCUCCGCGCUGCACGGCCAGCCGCCUUUGUCCGGGAGGACAGACAGAAACGCAGCAAGGCACACACCAAGGCUGCCGGGGAGGCCCGGGCACCGGACAGAUGCCUGUUGGGAAGCCAGGAGCUGCCGAGCCACGGACCACCUAACAGCCUCUCCGCCCGGAACGUGACAUAGAGAGUGUUGGCAUUAACUCGGGGGGUGUCCGAUUUCACUUCAGACCCCAAGUUUUUCUUUGUUUGUUUAAACAUGGAAUUCAGACUUCAUUGUACACCUGAGACAGACACAAAAGGGAUCAUGUAUUUUUGAGGAUUUUACCUGUUGACGUCUGAUGACCGGCCGUAGGUCCAGGGUUCCCGCUGGGUUUAAUCCCCUCGAAGAGUAAACCUGCCGCUCUGUCUGAUAACUUCAAGUAAGAGCAGCGGCUUCCUGGGUUGGCGUUCGCGGUGGAAGGUUCCUAGGAUGAAAGGUGAGCCUGGAUCCGCCGGCCGCAGACAUCGCGCUGCUGGGGACGAUUGGGGCCGCUGCUCUGCAGACCAGACCUUCCCGAAUUAUCCGUGGCUCCGAUGUCCCGGUGCUGACGGCCACAUGGGGACCUAACAGUGCCAAACGCCAUCUGCUCCAGCUGCUUUUUCACCCAGUUGCAGAGUCCUCACCACUCCCACAUUGAUCUGCUGUUUUCAAUUGGAACCAUUUCUCCUGCCUGAAACUCCAGGGCCCCUCCCUGGGCUGUCCGUGAGCAGGAGACCCCACCCCAGCAGCAGUGGUGAGCAGGCCUGUGCCUCCACGCCCAGCCCCCGCCAACGCGACUGGUUUUGUUUGCCACACGGUGAGAACCGGAGGACGGGAUGCUCCAGCCAGUUGGGUGGUUCUGGGGUCCCUGAGGAAGCCCCCUCCUGCACUUCCAUUAAGACAGCCAGUGGUUCCUGGAUCUUUGUCACCAAGCAGCGUUGAGCCAGAGCUGUCUAAUGCUGAGCCCAGCUCAGGAAGGAGAGAGGAGUCCUUCAGUGUGUCUUGGAGAUGCGAAGUGCGUCCUCGUAAAGGUCAGCUGUCAGUUUUGCUGGCCGCUCCGGCGCUGGCUCUCCUGUCCGGGACCACAACGAGAAACAGCGACAGAUUCGACGCAGAGCUCCGGAAGUGCCUGAGGAGCAGUGGUUCUUGGAAAUCGCCCGUCCUCCGCAUCACAGCCUCUCACCAGCAAAGCAGCCUCUGCCCAGGCCCUGGCGGGAGAGCUGCAGAGGGACCCAGGUGCCUGGAGGGCAUUUGAGGGAGGUGGCUGGACAGGUGUCUCCCUGAAGAAGAAGGGAGAACACUUUUCAAAGUGAUUCCGAGGCAGUGCGGGAGGACACACGUGCUGUGCAGUGGAGUGGGGUCGCCCGUGGCCCCCAUCAGAGUCCCCGUCCCCCAGGACAAGUGCAGAACCUCUGUGGGCCCCCUCCUUCCACCUAGAUAGAGAAAACCCCUUGUUCGGUUUCCUUCCCGUGUCCCGUUGUUUUUCUAAGCCCCCCGAAUUGAGUCGUUUCUAUGGCACUAACCUUUCCAUGGGAAAUAAGCUCUUUGUGGAAGUCCGUACCUGUUGCCCUGGGUGAGGUUUCAGAGAAACGGGGGCAGGAUGAACACAGCCGGCUGUCCUGGGUGCAGUUACGUCCGUGGAGGGUGAGAGAUUGCGCCCCGUUCCACACUUGUGUCGCCUGCUGUUGUCUGUGGGCCUUUUCUUUCCGUGGUGCCUGGUGUGUGCGUGCAUGGCGUGAGAGAACGGGGGGUGGGGGUUGGAGGUGGCUCCCCGACACCGGUGCCUGUGUGGCCUGAGCCGGCGCCCUCCCGGGAGCGCCCGUCACGGGGGGCCUCUGUGAUUACCUGCUGCUGCUCUCUCCCGCGUGGUGACUAUAUGUCCUCAGGGCUGCCUGUGGCCACCCUGAUGGGAGACCUCUGUUUGCUUCUGGGCCACUGCAGGUUGGCCUCCUCAAUACAAGCUGAUGUCUGCAGGGAGCGCCGCGUGCUGGGAUUGCACCACGUGUUGGUCACAAAUCGAGGUCGCCUUUUGGCCUGGUCUGCUCAGGCUGGCCCUGACCCACGUGGUUUCCUGGCUUCUGAGACGCAGCGCAUUCUUCCUGUUAGCGGUAGCGUUCUCUGAUUUCACUGCUUCAUUGCCAAGGGCGUGGAAAGGGGGUGGUGGAUGGAGCCGGGAGGUGGCGAGCACAGGACCCCGGGGCUGCAUUCUGCCGUGUGGGGUUCUGCACUGUCUAGCUUCUGCGGGGACUGCAAAGAGGGAUGAAGGGACGUGGUCCUAGGGGUCGGCUCAGACUCGGAGCAGGGCAGGGAGAGGAGGGCAAGGAGAGGAGGCCUGGGUCCUGGAUCCACUGCUCUGGGCUCAUAACCAUGAGAUUUUGAAAGAGUUUUUGGUCAUCUGAGCAGGUACCAUGCCUGGCUCAUGCCGGAACUUGUCUUGGAACCGGUAGCCAGAGGCCCAGGAAGGGACAGGGCCCAAAAGGGUUGCAUGUCCCGGCCACAAAGCCCUCCCUGUGUGCCCUGAGCCAGCCCAGCAAGCGCCUCCCAGCCAGGCGCUUUCGCAGAAGCAAGAGCACAGGCCAGGGGGACCGGGAGAGCCUCAGCCCCCAGCCUGGGCGGCCUGUGACCCUGAGCCGUGUGGAGCCAGGACCCAAGAACCUUCUCUAGGUUCUCAAGGGUGAGCUGACCCGGGCAAUGUGCAGGAAUGUGGGGAGCAAAAGUAGCUGAUUCCAGCCCCGUUCUGGGGUCACUGGGGAGGCAGAGGCUGAGGGCCUGUUCUCUGGUCACCAGGGACUGGGGGCACGGUCCACAGCGGAUGAGAACAGCAGGUCACAGUAGUGGCUUUGGGAAGGGCCCCUCCUGCUUUGCCCUGUUCGGAAAGGGGCUCCCUCAGAGCCCCUGGGCCCAGUAACCCGCUUCUGUCUCCUGACUCCUGCUGGAUAAAUUGCCAGGUUUAUCAAAUACAAGAAAACACCUGCUUUGGCUAGGAGGUAAGUCCCAAAAAGAACGUCUUAAGUAGAGCAAAGGCAUCCACCGAGGCCAUUUGGUGGCCCCUGGGAAGUGGGGAAGCAGGGCCUGAGCGUCCCCAGGCUGCUAGGGCAGCAGCUGGCUCAGGGCACACUCUCUCGUGCCAGCUUCUGCCACCAGCCCAGUGUCCACGGAGCCGCGGGGCCAGAGGAGCUCAGGGAGACCUGGCUGUCUAGGGCAUGGUACCCAGUAUCCCGGUGUGUGCCCAUCCUCAGCCACUUGUGUCUUUCUUUCCAUGUGGGAGUUCUCCCGGUGACACCUGCCCUCCGUUGAGGGUGGAAUCUGUCACUCAUGCCUUUGAGGGACCCAGAUGGACCAUCCCUCUUCUGCUUGCUUUCUACAUUCCUAAAAACCUCAACGUUAAUCCCUCACCAGUCGGGCCGAGUGUGGCCUCAUGGUUCUGCCGCGGCCCAGUCUUCUCCCACUGGCUUCACGCUAGAGGGCGCCAUGCGCUCUGGGUGAAAUGAGACGCUGGUGUGGGGUCCCCAUGUAGAGACCCUCAGGUCCCUAUCCAGAGACCCUCCAGGCAGUGCUGGGAAGACACUGGUGGCGGGGACCAUGACCAGGCGGGUGGAGCCAUGUGUGUCUCACACCUGCCGCCCCUCACUUUCCUUCCCGAGGUCUGGUAGGUCCUCUUUGGGAUUUGCUGUUUAUUUGUAUCUCCCUUUUCUUUGAUUUAAGAACAAUGCCAAGUGAAAAAGCUGGGAAUGAAUUUCUGAGUUGCUGAGUGUUCCCUGCUCCUAGGUACCACGCUCUGUGCUUCUCAGGCAGGGAGGAGAUGGAUUCGGUGGAGUUGGGCCAGGACGGGGGCUUCACCCUGCCCCCUCCAGACUGCCGAAGCCCCCAAGAAGUUUUGAGCCCAGCUGGGCCUCGCCUCCCCGGCUCCUGGGUCCAUUUUCUGUACUGGUUUGAGAUCACAGGCAUCAUUCAGCGAAUGCUCUUGUGUCCUCUGCAUAAAGAGGGCCCUCCCUGGAGCACCCCCGGGGAGCUGGGACUCUCCAGAAAGCCCCGGGUGAGGGCUCCGUCUUGAGAGAGAGAGAAAUCCCUUCUUUGGGCGAUUCAGUGAGUUCAGGAGGAGGAGGAAGCUUUUCCUUGGCUUUGAAAUCAGUGUUUUUAUGGAGACAAAGAACAGACCUCAGUGGGAAAAAUGAAAACGUAAUGGAACACGGGGAGGUGUCGGAGAAGAAAGGAUUUUCCCCUUCGCUUUCAGAGCCGGCGGGAGUGCAGGUCUGUUUUGCUUCAGAAGCCUCACAUUCUGCUUUGCCCUUGAGUGACUUCAUGCGGGAUGAGGAACUGUUGACCCCUCUAGAGAGGACACCCCAAGUCCAUCCUGGGCUCCUCCUCACCCCUCUGAGAAAGCCCCCCUAAAAAAAGGCUUCAGAGUCACCGGCAUGCCGCCUCACGUUGCAGGACGGAAUCGCGCGCUCCUCACGCUGGAGUAAGUUACGAAACAUGAUCGUCAGGCUCUUUGCAAACGCAGAGCCCCAGAACGCUGGAUGGAGGCCUCCUCGGCCCUGCGGGCGGCCUGGCUGCGGUAGGUCUGCUGCAAGGAGCCACCACGGGGACUGCGCCACACUCCUGAUGAAAACGUGUUUACCCACAGCCUCGCCUCGAGCCUCCUUGACAAUACCGCUGCUUCAAAGCAAUAUUAUUUAAUGAGAAUACUUUACAUUGCUCACAUGUGCUGCUAUGAAGACAGGAUUAGUCUGUAGACGGGACUCAGCUCCAGAGGUUCCUGGGUAAUGUAUUGUGGCUCUUGGAAAUGAGGGUAGAAUUUGAAAUAUAACAAAUGGUCUCUCGCCCGGUUCUGUCCCUUAUUUUUAGAUUGUUUUCCUGCAUCUUACAAUUUCCUUUUCUUUUCAAAGUUCCUUUCUCCAGGCCUGUUUUUCAGUGCUCAGGACACGGUUUUCAUCACAUACUUACUGUUUUUUUGGUUGGGUUUUGAUACGAAAAGCUGCUACGUUUGGUGACCAGAGGGAGGGUUUGGAAUCUGUGCUUUGCAGGGGAUCUCGGUGGGUACCGCGGCCCCUCGCAGGGUGGCGAGUGGGGUCCGUGCCUCGAGAAGGGGGCCCUUACCCACACCGUGCGGCUUGAAUUCUGUCGGAGUUGAAUCUGUGGAAAGGAUUGUCCCAUUAGAGCUGCUGCGUCCUUUCCUCUGUCCUCCCUGUCACCCAAACCCCGAAGUCACAGCUGCUUAGAAGAAUGGGAUUUUGGGGAUACAACCACACACAUUUCCCUCUGGACUGAAAUUUUAAAAACAGACCCAUUUCACUGACUUCUUUUUUUUUUUUUUUUUUUUUUUUUUUUUGAGACGGAGUCUCGCUCUGUCGCCCAGGCUGGAGUGCAGUGGCGUGAUCUCGGCUCACUGCAAGCUCCGCCUCCCGGGUUCACGCCAUUCUCCUGCCUCAGCCUCCCGAGUAGCUGGGACUACAGGCGCCCGCUACCACGCCCGGCUAAUUUUUUGUAUUUUUAGUAGAGACGGGGUUUCACCGUGUUAGCCAGGAUGGUCUCGAUCUCCUGACCUCGUGAUCCGCCCGCCUCGGCCUCCCAAAGUGCUGGGAUUACAGGCGUGAGCCACCGCGCCCGGCCCACUGACUUCUUUAGGGAAAAUAGUUUCAGUCUUGGGUUGUCUUGUGAGCCCACGGGCAUGGGACCCUGUCUCUGCUGGGCUUUUCCGGCCCCGUCCCAGCUCCUCCUCAGGCAGAGGCUGCAGCCCUCAGCUCUGCUGCUGGAUGGAACAUUUCAACCCCCUCCGGGAAGGUGGGCAGGGUGGAGGGCCCAGGGCUAGGCCUGCCAUGCACCAUGAGCAGGGGUGCUACCUGGGUGUGUGAAGUUGGGCUGGCUUUUCCUGGAGGUGGGUGAGAAGGCUCUCCGGGCAAAUCAGAAGGCCACGAGAGAGAGAGGAGCGGGGAGAGUGGUGAGGAGGAUUCGUCUCUGACUGAUGAACCUCGCCGUGCCUGUCUGUCACAUCCAAGUCUGUGCCAGCUGCUGGGAGGUCAGACUCCUGCCCUGAGAAACAGCCCAGUCCUUGGAGAAUGAAACCCUGAGGGUCAGUGAGUGGAGGCCUUCCCUCGGGGCCAGCCAUUCCCGGGAGGCCUGAGUGUGACCUGGAAGCUCUGUGGGUCACCAAGACUGGCAUUUUCCUUGUAUUUUUGUGCAGGGCUGAAGUGAGCGUUCCUCCUCUGAAUUGGUGAGGCUUUGGAAAUUUUUUGUUUCUUCUACUCAUCCUAAUGGCUGGUUUUGGCUGCCCGGAGUAUCAGAGAAUAUCACUAAGAGGGCAGUCAGUUUAUUUUUAGGCAUCUUUCUUUCUGUCCAGGGAGAAACCCCUCGGAAGAAUCUUAGUCACUCUUUGCACCUGCCCUGUCAUUCUCGCCAUGGGGAAAAUGCGUUGAAAAGAAAAAUACCGGGGCCAGGGAGAAGCCGUGAAUGUAUUUAUUUGCUUUGGUGAAGCUGCUGAACACUGGCUGCGGAGGGCCCCCCGCCCCCAUCCCGCUUCAGGCCCCAGUGACCCAGUUGCGUCUUAAGUUCCAUCGUCCAGAUUUCAGGCCACCAGAGGCUGCCAAAGGUGACUGAAGCGGUCUCCAAGUCACUCUGUCACCACUUUUUUUUUUUUUGAGAUGGAGUCUCGCUCUAUCGCCCAGGCUGGAGUGCAGUGGCCCAAUCUCGGCUCACUGCAACCUCCGCCUCCCAGGUUCGAGCGAAUUCUCCUGCCUCAACCUCCCAAGUAGCUGGGAUUACAGGCACCUGCCACCACACCCGGCUAAUUUUUGUAUUUCUAAUAGAGAUGAGAGUGUUACCAUGUUGGUCAGGCUGGUCUUGAACUCCUGACCUCAGGUGAUCUGCCCACCUCAACCUCCCAAAGUGCUGGGAUUAUAGGCAUGAGCCACCGCGCCUGGCCUCUGUCACUUUUUUUGCUCCUUACCCAGUUUUUGUUUUUUGUUGUUUUGUUUUGUUUUAGCGUGAUACUACAAUGGAAAGACUCCUAGUUGGUUAUUCUUUAUCUCGGAUUCUUUUUUCUGGAAUUGUUUGCUCAUUUGAGUGGUUGGUGGUUUGCCCUGUGUCAGACACGGUGAAAAGAGUGCAGGAAAGCUGGGGCCAGGGGAAGCGAAGUGGCUUCAAUCCGGGCUGACAGCCAAGAAGAGUUUUCCUCCCUUCGGUGACAGGGCCUGCCCCUCCGAGUCUAGAGGUAAAAGCAGCUUCUAGAACUGGCCCCUAAGUCUCCAAAUGUGUUGGCUAAGCUGAAAUGAGAGACUCUGAAUUAGAGUUUUUGUUUGUUUGUUUGUUCUCUGCAUGAAGUUCACAGGCCUGUAUGGAUGUUAAAUUGUGUCUAUAGCCUCUAAAUCUCCAGGUUAACUGGUCCAGAUUUUUUUUUUUUAAUCAGUAACAAUGGGAAUUUAAAAUCAAAUAUUUGGCCAGGUGCGGUGGCUCAUGCCCGUAAUCCCAGCACUUUGGGAGGCCGAGGCAGGCGCAUCACCUGAGGAGUUUGAGACCAGCCUGACCAACAUGGUGAAAUCCUGUCUCUACUAAAAAUACAAAAAAUUAGCCAGGCGUGGUGGCGUGUGCCUGUAAUCCCAGCUACCAGGGAGGCUGAGGCAUGAGAAUCGCUUGAACCUGGGAGAUGGAGGUUGCAGUGAGCCGAGAUCAUGCCACUGCACUCCAGCCUGGGCAACAGAGGGAGACUCUGUCUCAAAAAUAAUAAUCAAAUCAAGUAUUUUAAGUUUGGCUCUUCUUUUUUUCAAGAAAGGCUUUUUGGAUACCUAGAAUACCUUCAUGUAUGUGGCUUGAUUUCUGUUUCAGGAAAAGGGGGGCGGGAGGAGAGACAACAGCCGUGUUCCAGAGUCUGUCCUGAGAUGUCGCUGAGUCCAGACACUUGGGCUGCACGUGCCCUGCAGAUGACAAAGGCCGGCAGCUCAGCACACGUGCAGGAGGGGUUAAAGCCAAUAUUGAGUUUUUGUUCUUGUUGUUUUAAUCUGAACGAUUAUUCUCCUGUAAAAAUAAUUUGGGAGGGGCGGGUGUUGUUCGGUGUGUGUGUGUGUGUGUGUGUGUGUGUGUGUGUGUGUAUUUUUUUUUUUACAGUGGCGCCUGUCUAAAGUAUUUUUCACAACAUGUUUGAUAAUCAGUGCUUUAAAAAGCAGCAGUGUCCUAUGAAGUGGAAAUGUCAGUUCUAGAGCAUUGGAUGUGAAGUUCUGGUCAUGUCACCUUGCGUGUCUCACCCUGGAGGAGUGAAGGUGGGCGCCCGGCGGGGGGGUGUGGCUGCACCCCAGCACCGGGAGGGGGCACGCACGACACCAGAGGAAGGGACAGCCCCACCCAUGUCAACAGCAGGCAACCUGUGUUUUCAUUUCAAGUGGGAUACAGUAUUUUUUUAAUAAGGAGCCAUACUUUUUUUUAAGAGUUUGAGAUCUGAAUGUGAUUUCUAAUUGUAUCAGACGUUAAUGUUUUAAAGCUAUAACAAAGUUUAAAAUUUCUACUUUUUGUUUUUCAUUUAUUUUAACUGUUCUUUUAUCUAUUAAAUUGUUGUAUGUGGAUGGGGAAGUUUUGUUUCUCCUCUUAGCAUUUGUUUCUAUAACCAGAAAUAAAAUUCUAUAUUAAAGAAAUGA